UUUUUUUUUUUUUUUUUUUUUAAUCUUUCCUGGGAGAUGUGAUAGGGAAGAGAAGCCAGAGGGAGACUCUUCAGGUUGGGGGGAGCUAAAGGAGCAGUAGUAAGGAAGCUUGGAGUGGGAGGUGCCUUGGCCCCCGAGGAGGCCUUGGGGAUAGGCCCUCAUUGAUUAUGGCCCAGCCCCUCAGACCCUUCUCCUCUACCGUGCCCUCAGAGGGUCCCUCUGCUGUGGUCGUCCCUGGCUCUUAUACCCCCAGAGAGGCCUGGACCUCUCCCCAUUUUGUCAACUUUCUCUUCCUGACCAGCUGGGCCCCCUGCUCUCCCUGGUUGGCACUGGAUCCAGAAUCUCAGGACUUACGCUGGCCUGGUGUGGGCCCUUGGUUGGACACUUUGCCACACACCUGAGUACCUUUAUGGGGACAAGGGAAGUCCAGGAGCAAGUGGGUGGGCCCAACAUUUCCCUAGUUCUAUUUGAGUCAGGCCCCCUGCUUCUUUGCCCCUCUAGUCGAGAGAGUGGUGGCCUUACUGGAAAAGAGGAGUUGAGGGCCUUGACUUAAUACAGGCCUUGACCUCUUGGACACAGGUCAUCGUUGGUGUUCAUCAGGUUCUAUAAGUGGGUAUGAGGAUCCGAUGUGAGCCUGGAACCCAUCAUCAAGGGUCAGGUUCUGAGUCUCAUGGCACUGUGGUGCUGGGAUUCUCCCCAUCCCACGGGACCAUGGCUGGGACUCUCGAGGCUCUCUCAGGCCAGCUGGUUUGAGGCAACUAUCUCUUUUUUAUAGAGAAGGAGGAAAUGGUGGCAGGCCGGCACAACCUCAGCAUCACUGUAAUUGCUGGUGGCUUUUAUGAGCCAGUCAUGGGGCCGGAGUCCGGCCAACUGUCUGUCCUUCUGUCCCAGUUUGGUGACUUACUCAUGGAGGGAGGGGCGGUUAGGUACUAGAAGCUGUGUUCUAGAAGCUGGACGUCUGACUGUAUUGUGGUCGAUGUCACUCUGUCUAUCCAUGAUCACAGCAGGUAGGAUGGAGCUUAGACUUCAGGAAGAACUUCCCAGUGGGGAAGCUGGGGGGGAGAGAGAUGGCUCUAAUUUUGCAUAGGAAAGGAGGGGAACUCAAAGCACUUUCUUUUCCAGUGGCUCUCCCGAAAGGAAAGGCCUUGACCUUUGGCUUGGUGGGGUCGGUGCUAUUUGGAUCUCGGAAUAUUUAUCUUCUUUUUCCUCUCCCUGCUUAUGGCUGAAAGUAUUCUGAGGCGUUUGUCCUGGAGCUGUGGGAGAAAUAGCCAUUAGGCCCCUUUCCCCCAGUAGUGGGAGCUAGAUAAGGGUCUCAUGUAGACAGGCAUGCCCAAUGCAGUCCACAGCAUUUAGUGGUACACAUGCAGGAAAGUGUGCAACACAUACACACUGGUAUGUAGACACCCACAGAGCAGCUGCUGCACUGCGGGAGGUGGGGGGUAGUGAAUGGCAAAGAUGAUUAAAGGAUUGGAGAGUUGGGAUGGGGUUGAGGGGACCGGAGGCAAGAAGGCGAAGGGCAUAGCAAGAACUUUGAAGAGAGAAGGGCUGACUGGAGCAGGAGGGAUUAAGGUUAGACCACAGAUGGGCAGGCAGAGCCCUGUCUGCAAAAUAAAGAGCAUGGCUUGUGAGUCAAGGAGCCUUGGCUGACUUCCAUCCCUGCCCCUUACCCCUCCCCCACGUGCCCCUCUCUGUGUUCCUGGCACAGCCUGCCUCUGCCCCUCACACUGACCGUGUGUCCCCGGGUCCCUCCUCUUGGGCCCCAGCUUUCCAGAUGUACAGAGUUUCGCCUUUCGGUGAUUAACACCUGGGUGUUUUGGUGGUUUGUCGCUGGUCUCUGUUGCCCUCCCCGCUCACCCUGAUGAGCAAGGCCACUGUGAGGCAUCAAGACUACAUCUAAGCCAUCAGGCAUCUGGGGGUAGAUCCUUGGCCUAGGUGAUCCCCAAGGCCCUCUUCAUCUGACAUUUUCCUUUUCCUGAGGCUGAGGCUACAAGCCUCUCUUUCCUGAGAGCCAAGUUAUGCUUCUGGUUAGUCCUGGCUGGUGUGGAGACAGGGGAAUGCAUUCAUUGAUUCUGCACAGGACCCUGAUAGCCAAGGGGGCGGGAGGCACUUGUGCCUGUCUGACUUCUUUUCUUUCUGCUGUAGGCUGGGAGGGGAGGGACAUGUCCGAAGCUCUGGCCUGUCGCUGGCCACACCCAGGUGGGACCAUAUUUACUCAUUUAAACUUACCCUCCCAGGAGGCUCUGGGCUCUAGGCCUGGUCACUGACCUUGGCUUGGUGCCUCUGGCUGGAUGCUGUGGCCACUCUCCUAGGAGCUGAGCAGACGAGGAAACCAUGCAGAGGGAGCUUUUUUUUUUUUUUUUGCCCCCUGGUCAAAGGAGCUUUACCCUCAGCAUUACCCCUCUUGCCCAACUUUCCAGUAUACUUUGAAGACCAAAAACCACAACUUUUUAAUUUUUUUUGAGGUAGGAUCUUGCUCUGUUGUCCAGGCUCGAGUGCAGUGGUGCCAUCAUGGCUCACUGCAGCCUCCCAUUCAAGCGAUCCUCCGGCCUCAGCCUUCCAGGUAGCUGGGACUCCAGGUGUGAGCCAUCGUGCCCCGCCCAAAAACCAAAACUUUUGAGAUCCCAAUGAAGAGAGGUGAUGGGUUCUCAAAAGGGAGGAAGGAAACUUCCAUUUCUUAUGUUCCUGUGUGCCAAGCUUUGUACUGAGCAUGGGAAUAUAAGAAGACUGUUUCUCUCUAAAACUGUUUUUUUGAAUUGGGAAACUGAGUCUCAGAGAUGUAAGUGACUUUUAAGCUUUCCUAGUUAUGAAGUAUAAAGGGCUUUUGUCUGAGAUUAAAGGAGAGAUCCUGCCCUGCAGGACGGGGCAAUGGAAAGGAGGCCCACGGAGACCUGAGAGGAGGAGGAGAAAUUGAAGGGAAGAGAAAACCAGGAUUCCUCAGCAGAGGGCAGAGAAUCAGCCUUUGGUGGCAAGGAGGCUGUGCAGAAGGUAUCCUGCAGACCAUGAACUGAGCACUGUUCCCAGACCGUUCAUGAGCACAGUGUAAGGUGUGCCGAGACCCACCACCCAGCGAGCCCCUCCCCUCCGUAGCACUGAGGACCCCCGGAGAAGAUGGGGAGGAAAAAGAUUCAGAUCCAGCGAAUCACCGACGAGCGGAACCGACAGGUGACUUUCACCAAGCGGAAGUUUGGCCUGAUGAAGAAGGCGUAUGAGCUGAGCGUGCUAUGUGACUGCGAGAUCGCACUCAUCAUCUUCAACCACUCCAACAAGCUGUUCCAGUACGCCAGCACCGACAUGGACAAGGUGCUGCUCAAGUACACGGAGUACAAUGAGCCACACGAGAGCCGCACCAACGCCGACAUCAUCGAGACCCUGAGGAAGAAGGGCUUCAACGGCUGCGACAGCCCCGAGCCCGACGGGGAGGACUCGCUGGAACAGAGCCCCCUGCUGGAGGACAAGUACCGACGCGCCAGCGAGGAGCUCGACGGGCUCUUCCGGCGCUAUGGGUCAACUGUCCCGGCCCCCAACUUUGCCAUGCCUGUCACGGUGCCCGUGUCCAAUCAGAGCUCACUGCAGUUCAGCAAUCCCAGCGGCUCCCUGGUCACCCCUUCCCUGGUGACAUCAUCCCUCACGGACCCGCGGCUCCUGUCCCCCCAGCAGCCAGCACUACAGAGGAACAGUGUGUCUCCUGGCCUGCCCCAGCGGCCAGCUAGUGCGGGGGCCAUGCUGGGGGGUGACCUGAACAGUGCUAACGGAGCCUGCCCCAGCCCUGUUGGGAAUGGCUACGUCAGUGCUCGGGCUUCCCCUGGCCUCCUCCCUGUGGCCAAUGGCAACAGCCUAAACAAGGUCAUCCCUGCCAAGUCUCCACCCCCACCUACCCACAGCACCCAGCUUGGAGCCCCCAGCCGCAAGCCCGACCUGCGAGUCAUCACUUCCCAGGCAGGAAAGGGGUUAAUGCAUCACUUGAACAAUGCCCAGCGCCUUGGGGUCUCCCAGUCUACUCAUUCGCUCACCACCCCAGUGGUUUCUGUGGCAACGCCGAGUUUACUCAGCCAGGGCCUCCCCUUCUCUUCCAUGCCCACUGCCUACAACACAGAUUACCAGUUGACCAGUGCAGAGCUCUCCUCCUUACCAGCCUUUAGUUCACCUGGGGGGCUGUCGCUAGGCAAUGUCACUGCCUGGCAACAGCCACAGCAGCCCCAGCAGCCGCAGCAGCCACAGCCUCCACAGCAGCAGCCACCGCAGCCACAGCAGCCACAGCCACAGCAGCCUCAGCAGCCGCAACAGCCACCUCAGCAACAGUCCCACCUGGUCCCUGUAUCUCUCAGCAACCUCAUCCCGGGCAGCCCCCUGCCCCACGUGGGUGCUGCCCUCACAGUCACCACCCACCCCCACAUCAGCAUCAAGUCAGAACCGGUGUCCCCAAGCCGUGAGCGCAGCCCUGCGCCUCCCCCUCCAGCUGUGUUCCCAGCUGCCCGCCCUGAGCCUGGCGAUGGUCUCAGCAGCCCAGCCGGGGGAUCCUAUGAGACGGGAGACCGGGAUGACGGACGGGGGGACUUCGGGCCCACACUGGGCCUGCUGCGCCCAGCCCCAGAGCCUGAGGCUGAGGGCUCAGCUGUGAAGAGGAUGCGGCUUGAUACCUGGACAUUAAAGUGACGAUUCCCACUCCCCUCCUCUCAGCCUCCCUGAUGAAGAGUUGACAAUCUCACCGCCCGCCCUUCCCUGCCCCGGGCUCCUCCCGCUCGACCCCCACUUCCUUUCUUGUGCUUCGUGUCCUGUUGACGGUUACAUUUGUGUAUAAUUAUUAUAUUAUUAUUAUUAUUAUUAUAUUUUUUUUAAUUUGGAUUCUCGCUUUGGAGAGGGGGAUGCUCUCAUCCCCUCUUUCUGUACCCCCCACCAUUUUCACUGGCUGGGGGGCUCUCUUUUUCGCGGGAAGGGGGGACACUUUGCACGUUGUACACAUAUGCUGCAGGAAGGGGGUGGGGGGCCCAAUAAGGCCUUUGGGAAAGGACAGGUGCCGAGCCCUGCAUGUGGAGCCCUCCCACCCCACCCCCAGAUAGAGGGAAAUAACCAAAAAACUACCAAACAACAGAAACCCACACUCUAGACUGAAACCCCAAAGUGGGCUUGAUGGGUGGGUUUGUGUUUCAAGGGGAAAGUGAGGCAGAGGUUCUGAAAAGGGUCUCUGUUUUUGUGUUCAUGUAGCCAUAGGCACAUGGAGCAGAAUACUUAAGCCUGGCCCCCAAAUGCCCCUGCACACACACGUGCCACACCUGCGCUGAUUCUUGUGUGUGCUGCACCCCCAAGGUGUGUGGGUGCUGGCUGAGCUUUGGGCCGGGAAGGCAGCCUGGGAAUCUGAGGCUGGAGACAGGGGUUUGAGGUGGGGGCCUCUCUGGAAGCACAUUUGGAGGGAAAGACAAGAGAGCCAUGAGGAGAGGGCUGAGGAGGGCAGAAGGGCUAGGCAGGGGGCAAAUUGAGCCCCUCCCUUCCCCAGUUUUUCUCUAAGAUAUACAGUGCAAUAGCUCCCCACCCCUCAGUUGACGCCAGCCCUGUAAAGCUGGCCACAGUGUGCAGGGAGAAUGGGGAGAGGGUCUUCAGUGAGGUGGCUGGGGCGAGAGUCGGCCUGGACUUCCCUGGGGUGCUCCAGGCCAGAGCUCUUUCAUUGGGGCGAGUGUGGUGAGGGGACGUCCUUGGUCUUGCACGCACACUACCUGGGGGAGUCAACACUGGGAUGGUCUGUGGGGUGGGAGGGCCUACGGAUGGGUCCGUAGAGGUCCCACCUCCCUCAUUCCUCCUUGGCCCCUCUCCCUAGCUUCUCCUGUUAGCUCCUUCUGCUCCUGACCCCACCUCCUUGCUCUUGGCGCCCCUAUUGUCUCUGGCUACCUCCUUGUCCCACCACCUCCAGGCUGCAUCCCACCUUCCCUCUUGGCUACUGUAAUUGUAAAUAGCGACCUUUGGAAAACGUUAGCGGUGUAACAGUCCAGGAAACUGUUUUUUUUUGUUGUUGUUGUAUUGAUAUGAAAUGAGAUUCUAUUUUUGUCAAAGUAUAUUGUAAUAAUAAUGACUCAAACGGCCCGUACUGUACAGACGAGAUUCUUCUGCUGUUGUUCUUGCUCCCCUCCCCUCCUCUGAGUCCGCCCCUCCCUGCUGCCUCCUCAGUGGGGCAGUGGGCAAGGGGCCCAGGGGCAGCCGAAGCACGGGGUCCUGAGACCUCAGGCAGGAUUGGAGAUCAAACCAGAGGGGGCAGGCCCCCAGCCUGCUCUCUAGGAUCACCCCCCGCCCUAAGGGGCCUGGCCUGGGGUGACGUGGCCAGGCAGACUGUCUGCCCCACUCCUUCACACAAGCCCAGCUCCUCUGCCCAAGGGGUGCGGCGCCCCCUUGGGGUUUCCUCCCAGUUGGAGAGUAGAGUUAAGACAAGGCCCAGUUUUGUGUUAGCCGACCGUCUUUGCCCACCUCUAUGACCCAGCCUCUUGCAGUAUUCCCAUACUUGAUGCAGGGAAGGAACCAGAAGCAGAGGGGCCUCUACGCAGGUACACACGUGUACCUGAGUGUGUUCAUGAGGGCAUCUGGUGUUUAUGUGUCUGAGUGUAGCUUUGUAUUUAUGUGUGUGUGUGUGUGUAUGUCUGAUUGCACGGGUGUACUUUUGUAUUUAUGUGUGUGUGUGGUUGCACGGGUGUGCCUCUGUGUGUCUCUGACCCUGGCUGGGUGUGUGUGCAAAUCUGUGUGACUGGAGCUCUAGGGGCAUCUCUGUGUCUGAGUGUGCCUGGUGUGUGUUUACAAAGGGAGAGUUGGCUGCUCCAGCUCCACAGCCCUGGGACCCCAACUCCUGUCUUCCCUGCUCCUUUCCCUGUGUUCACCCUCAGCUCUGACACAUUGAACUGCAGUUGGGGGGAUUGGCAGUUAGCCCUCUGUGCUUCUCCCUGCAGCCCUACCUCUGCCAAGGUCUCUCCCUCCAGGGACCUCUGCUUCCACCCACAUAUGUCCACUUAGUCACCCACACUUGACACAGUUCCUGGAGUACCCUCUUCCCCCAACCCCAGACCUGCUUUCAGAGCAAAACUCAAGUCCCUCUUCCUCCGUGAAGCUUCUCCCUCAGCUGAGCAGUGAUCACUUACUCACUCUUAACCCCAAUCCGCUGACUGGGUGGGGACAGCACGUCCAGCCUUCCCACCUCUCCUGCAGGCUUCUAGACGGAGUUUCAAAAACUGAUGAGCCUCGAUCCAGGGCUUGAAAGAAGCCAGGGUGUAAUCUUGUUCAUGCAUGCGUCCCCAGAGCCUCGCCCAGUGCCUGGCACAUAGUAGGCACUCAAUAAAUGCUGAAUGGGUGAAUAGUUGAAUGAUAGGUGCUCAAUAAAUGAAUGAAUGGCCUUCCCUUCUCAGGCUAUUCCCACCAUUAGUCUGCCCACCUUUCUAGGCUGGGCUUGGCCACCAUUAAACACGGGGUGGGGGUGAGGGCCCCUGCAAUUCACGGUGCAAUAUUCACCAGUUUUGCCCUCUGCCUCAUAAAGGCAAACCUGGCUUUUGAUUACCAUGUGUGGAUGUUUCAGUGUCCUUUCUUCUCUGUCCCUGGGGAUGGGGUGGUCUGUGAAUAUGUGACAUUUCUGCAGUUCAGUAUCCGAAGGUUUCUCUUGGGGGUAGGGGCUCCUGGGCGGCCAGAUGAAUGGGUCCCUGGGAACCCAGACCUCAGAUGAGGACUUAAUGUCUUCUUCCUCUCAAGCCAAAUUCGCCUCCACCCACUCCCUCUGAAGAACUGGGCAUUUGCCAAAGUAACCACUGGAGUCAUCUAAUGGCCCUCCCCCUCCCCAGGUUUCCCACAGCUUUCAGGGACAGUGGGCAAGAGGACACCCCCCCCCACCACCUCAGUGGAACACACCAUUCUCCCCCCCUCAACAGCACACUCAGUGCAGCAAGACUGACCCCUGACCCCCUCCCAGCCCUCCCUACCUUGGACAGGAAGGAAGUAAUGCACCUUCUCUUGCUGAUUAUUUAUUUGUUUGGAGAGACAGAAAUGUAAAAGUGUAUCUAGAAAUAUCUAUAUCUCUAUAUAUUUUUAACUGACUCUUUGGAAUCCCCUGGGGUGGGGUGAGGGGUAAGUUUAGGCUUUCGCGGAGGGGAGGAGACAUGGAGCCUGGGAACUCCUUGUUCUCCCCUCUGCUGCCUCUCCCCACCCCUUAAAGCAGUUGGUAGAAGGAAUGGUAUUUGUAUGGGGGGAGGGAGGCUGGAAUGGAGAAUCUGGAUUCUCUCCUCUUCCCCAUUCUCCAGAGGGAGGGAGGUGGUGAGGAAGAGGAAGGGAGGGGCAGGAUGGGCCAUGGAGGUGCCCCACCCCCACACCUGACAAUCACCCACACUCCUGGGGCUCUUCCUGGGUCCUGGGGCAGGGCGAGUCCAAGUGUGAGGCUGUUGAUUUGUUUUCAAUAUUUCUUUUCGUGCUGUAUGGUGAUGCUUUCUUAGUAUUCUACACAAUAAGAAAAGACAAAGUCCUCGAGAUUCUUAUGAGUUUUGUUUGAAAACUCUUUCACUAUAUUUGUUGUAAAGAGGUUUACUAUUAAAAGAAAAAGAAUACACGUUUCUGAUA